AGUGCGGACGUCGCCAUUCCUGGCCCAUGGGAAGAUUGCGUUUCACCUGCUCCUGAAGGCCGAAGGUGGCUCUAGCGCAUCCUUUGUCGCGCCGUGACCUGCAGGUACUGACAGAUCCGUAGGGAGGACACCGUGACUUCCCGGACGCUGGGAAAUGGACUCAGUCUCCUUUGAGGAUGUGGCCGUGAACUUCACCCUGGAGGAGUGGGCUUUGCUGGAUUCUUCACAGAAAAAGCUCUAUGAAGAUGUGAUGCAGGAGACCUUCAAAAACCUGGUUUGUCUAGGAAAAAAGUGGGAAGACCAGGACAUUGAAGAUGACCACAGAAACCAGGGGAAAAAUCGAAGAUGUCAUAUGGUUGAGAGACUCUGUGAAAGUAGAAGAGGUAGCAAAUGUGGAGAAACCACUAGCCAGAUGCCAAAUGUUAAUAUCAACAAGGAAACUUUUACUGGAGCAAAACCACAUGAAUGCAGCUUUUGUGGAAGAGACUUCAUUCAUCAUUCGUCCCUUAAUAGGCACAUGAGAUCUCACACUGGACAGAAACCAAAUGAGUAUCAGGAAUAUGAAAAGCAACCAUGUAAAUGUAAAGCAGUUGGGAAAACCUUCAGUUAUCACCACUGCUUUCGCAAACAUGAAAGAACUCACACUGGAGUGAAGCCCUAUGAAUGUAAACAGUGUGGGAAAGCCUUUAUAUAUUACCAGCCAUUUCAAAGACAUGAAAGGACUCAUGCUGGACAGAAACCCUAUGAAUGUAAGCAAUGUGGAAAAACCUUUAUAUAUUACCAGUCUUUUCAAAAACAUGCUCAUACUGGAAAGAAACCCUAUGAAUGUAAACAGUGUGGGAAAGCCUUUAUAUGUUACCAAUCUUUUCAAAGACACAAAAGGACUCACACUGGAGAGAAACCCUAUGAAUGUAAGCAAUGUGGUAAGGCUUUCAGUUGUCCCACAUACUUUCGAACUCAUGAAAGAACUCACACUGGAGAAAAACCCUACAAAUGUAAAGAAUGUGGUAAAGCCUUCAGUUUUCUCAGUUCUUUUCGAAGGCAUAAAAGGACUCAUAGUGGAGAGAAACCCUAUGAAUGUAAAGAAUGUGGAAAAGCCUUCUUUUAUUCUGCAAGCUUUCGAGCACAUGUAAUAAUACACACUGGGGCUCGACCUUAUAAAUGUAAAGAAUGUGGGAAAGCCUUCAACUCUUCUAAUUCCUGUCGAGUGCAUGAAAGAACUCAUAUUGGAGAAAAACCAUAUGAAUGUAAACGAUGUGGCAAAUCAUUCAGUUGGUCCAUUUCUCUUCGAUUGCAUGAAAGAACUCAUACUGGAGAGAAACCUUAUGAGUGUAAACAGUGUCAUAAAACCUUCAGUUUUUCAAGUUCCCUUCGAGAACACGAAACAACUCACACUGGAGAGAAACCCUAUGAAUGUAAACAAUGUGGUAAAACCUUCAGUUUUUCAAGUUCCCUUCAAAGACAUGAAAGGACUCACAAUGCAGAGAAACCCUAUGAAUGUAAACAGUGUGGGAAAGCCUUCAGGUGUUCAAGUUAUUUUCGAAUUCAUGAAAGGUCACACACUGGAGAGAAACCCUAUGAAUGUAAACAGUGUGGAAAAGUUUUCAUUCGUUCCAGUUCCUUUCGACUGCAUGAAAGAACACACACUGGAGAGAAACCCUAUGAAUGUAAACUAUGCGGUAAAACCUUCAGUUUUUCAAGUUCCCUUCGAGAACAUGAAAAAAUUCACACUGGAAAUAAGCCUUUUGAGUGUAAGCAAUGUGGUAAGGCCUUCCUUCGUUCCAGUCAAAUUCGAUUGCAUGAAAGGACUCACACUGGAGAGAAACCGUAUCAAUGUAAACAAUGUGGAAAAGCCUUCAUUUCUUCCAGUAAAUUUCGAAUGCAUGAGAGAACUCACACGGGAGAGAAACCCUAUCGAUGUAAACAAUGUGGGAAAGCCUUCAGAUUUUCAAGUUCUGUUCGAAUUCAUGAAAGGUCUCACACUGGAGAGAAACCUUAUGAAUGCAAACAAUGUGGAAAAGCCUUCAUUUCUUCCAGUCACUUUCGACUGCAUGAAAGGACUCAUAUGGGAGAGAAAGUCUAAGAAUAUAAGCAACAUUCUGAAGCCUUCGGUUGUUCCAGCUCCUUCUGAAUACACAAAAGAGUUCAUACUGGACAGAAGCUGUGUGAAUACAAACAUUGUUCUAAAGCCCUUAAUUGUUCCAGUUUCUUUUGAGCACGAAAGAAUUCCCACUGGUGAGAAACAGUAUGAAUGUAAACAUUGUGAUUAAGCCUUCAGUUGACCUAAUUCAUUUCAAAGACAGGACUCGUGCUGCAGUGAAAUCUGUUUUGUUUUUUGUUUUUUGUUUUUUUAAAAAAGGCCAAGCUUGUUGGCUCAUGCCUAUAGUCCCAGCACUUUGGGAGGCCAAGGUGCAAGGCAGGCAGAUCAUUUGAGGUCAGAAAUUCGAGACCAGCGUGGUCAACAUGGUGUAACCCCAUCUCUACUAAAAAUUACCAAAAAAUGAACCAGGCAUGGUAGUGCAUGCCUCUAAUCCCAGCUACUCAGGAGGCUAAGGCAGGAGAAUCACUUGAACCUGGAGACAGAGGUUGCAGUGAGCUGAGAUCACGCCACUGCAUUCCAGCCUGUGCGACAGAAUGAGACACUGUCUCAAGAAAAAAUAAAAGUGGGAAAAUCUUCCAACUGUCCUCUAGAGUGUGAAUAUAUGAAAGGAGUCAGAGUGGGGUGAAAGUCUAUAAAUGUAAGACAUUUGGGAAAGCCUUCACACAGCCUUUUGAGCACACAUGAGAAUGUAUACUGGAGAGAAACCCUAUAAAUAUUAAGAAUGUGGGAAAUUCUUCAUCCUAGUUCUUUUGUUGUUGUUGAUGAUACAAAAAUAUUUUCAUUUAAUAAAGAUUGUCAGGUUAUAUUUAAUAAGAAAGAAAGUAUCAUGUAAACAGCCCAGUAAUAAAAUUUUACAAUCUUA